AGUGGCUCACCCUCAGUCAACAGGCCAGACUCAAGGGGUUCCUGGCAAGUCAUUUCUCCCUCAGGCCUUCGGUUUCCUCACCUACAAGAUGAGAGGGCUGGACCAGAUGGCAAUUCGGGAGGGUCCGUAUCUCCUGCUGGGUGAGGUCCUUGGACACAGCGCACUUGGUGCGCAGCCCGCGCAGGCUGCCAAUGGAGAUGCCGAUGAGCUUCUGGAGCUGCCCGCACUGCUGCAGCGCCCGGCUGGCCGCGGCCCCUGUGCCUCCCUACGCGAUAGCCGCGUCACCCCCGCCACUGCCCUCCUUCUUCUCUCCCAUUGCAGCCGAGCGCAGCGCCGCUCUAUGCGGGCUGCAGCAGCCCAGGAGCGGAGCCCUGGGCGCCGGCGUCUAGGCAAGGAACCCCUGAUUCGGGAGAGCUGGACCAGGAGCGCCCCUUGGCGCUGCCUUAGUCAGGACGCCGGUAGAGCUGGCAGCCAAGUCUGCGGAUCCAGCCCUCAGACCCGCGGCGGUGGGGGCAAAAAACUGCAGCGGCAAAAAGCUACGGUGAUGGGCGCAAAAAGCCGUAAAAAGCCGCAGCAUUGGGGGCAAAAAGCCGCGACGGCGGGGGCAAAAAGCCCGGGCGGUGGGGGCAAGAAGCCGGGGCAGGAAAAACCUGCGGCGACAGGGGAAAAAACUCGCGCCGCAAAAAGCCGGGGCGGCGGGGGCAAGAAGCCGCGGCGGGAAAAACCUGCGGCGGCGGGGGCGAAAAAUCCCCAAAAAGCCGCGGCAGCAGGGGCUAAAUUCCGCGAGGCCGGGGGCAGAAAGCCGCGGUGGCGGGGGCAGAAAGCAACGGAGGCGGGGGCAAAAAGUCGAGGCGGCGGAGGCAUAAAGCCGCAAAAACCCGCAGCAGCGGGGGCAAAAAUCCAUGGCGGCAAAAAGCCGCGUCGGCGGGGGCAAAGUAGUGGAAAUGGGGUAGAAGGCCAGAACAGCUUGGCAUUCCUGGAGUGUGAUGUGGAAGGAAAAGUGCAGAGGAAGACAAACAAAGAUAAUCCGAGAAGGGAAAGCAGCAGAUGCACUGGUUCCCAGGUUCUUGGCAUCCUACAGAGAGAAACUUGUUUGAGCUAG